AUACACAGAAAUGGGGACUGCGAGCAGAAGCAACAUCGCUCGCCAUCUGCAAACCAAUCUCAUUCUAUUUUGUGUCGGUGCUGUGGGCGCCUGUACUCUCUCUGUCACACAACCGUGGUACCUAGAAGUGGACUACACUCAUGAGGCCGUCACCAUAAAGUGUACCUUCUCCGCAACCGGAUGCCCUUCUGAGCAACCAACAUGCCUGUGGUUUCGCUACGGUGCUCACCAGCCUGAGAACCUGUGCUUGGACGGGUGCAAAAGUGAGGCAGACAAGUUCACAGUGAGGGAGGCCCUCAAAGAAAACCAAGUUUCCCUCACUGUAAACAGAGUGACUUCAAAUGACAGUGCAAUUUACAUCUGUGGAAUAGCAUUCCCCAGUGUGCCGGAAGCGAGAGCUAAACAGACAGGAGGAGGGACCACACUGGUGGUAAGAGAAAUUAAGCUGCUCAGCAAGGAACUGCGGAGCUUCCUGACAGCUCUUGUAUCACUGCUCUCUGUCUAUGUGACCGGUGUGUGCGUGGCCUUCAUACUCCUCUCCAAAUCAAAAUCCAACCCUCUAAGAAACAAAGAAAUAAAAGAAGACUCACAAAAGAAGAAGAGUGCUCGGCGUAUUUUUCAGGAAAUUGCUCAAGAACUAUACCAUAAGAGACAUGUGGAAACAAAUCAGCAAUCUGAGAAAGAUAACAACACUUAUGAAAACAGAAGAGUACUUUCCAACUAUGAAAGGCCAUAGAAACGUUUUAAUUUUCAAUGAAGUCACUGAAAAUCCAACUCCAGGAGCUAUGGCAGUGUUAAUGAACAUAUAUCAUCAGGUCUUAAAAAAAAAUAAAGGUAAACUGAAAAGACAACUGGCUACAAAGAAGGAUGUCAGAAUGUAAGGAAACUAUAACUAAUAGUCAUUACCAAAAUACUAAAACCCAACAAAAUGCAACUGAAAAAUACCUUCCAAAUUUGCCAAGAAAAAAAAUUCUAUUUUAAACUUGUAUCCUGAGUCUGUUUCAUUCAACAUGAGAUGUGUGAUGACUGCCAUCCUGAAGAUCUGAAGCCAAACCAUGUGCCUCAGUCUUGAGUGGAAGAAUCACCUUUAUGGUUUGUGGAAAUCAUGGCACAAUUAAAAUAAGUUGGGAGGGACAACGUGACAAAAUUUGAGUUAGAGACAUUCAUUUUGAAAAGCACCUUAGUAAAGUUAUUUCCUCUGAUGUUGUAAUGGGGCAGUGGGGUAACGCACAUUUGCCUGCCAGGGUAUGCAAAGUAACUUACAUCAUGCUAUCAGCAAAAUGAGAAUAAUAUAGUGGCUAGAGUAAGACCAUAAAAGCCAAAAUACAGAAAAUCCAAAGCUGAAGGUUAAACAGAGGUAACUUCAGAACAAAUAAGCCACAACGGACUCUAGAUGUCAGUGUUGUGCCAAAUAACAGCACCAGGGAAGAUGUGGGCAACACAUCUACUUUACAAGCACGUUUGUAAUACUGAUUUUUUUUCUUUUCUUUUUUUUUUUUUUUUGAGACAGAGUCUCGUUCUGUUGCCCAGGGUGGAGUGCAGUGGUGCAAUCUCGGCUCACUACAACCUCCACCUCCCGGGUUCAUGCCAUUCUUCUGCCUCAGUUUCCCAAGUAGCUGGGAUUACAGGUACGCACCACCACGCCCGGCUAAUUUUUUUUUUUUUUUUUUUUUGUAUUUUUAGUAGAGACGGGGUUUCACCAUGUUGGCCAGGCUGGUCUCAAACUCAAGACCUCAGAUGAUCUGCCUGAAAUGGCCUCCCAAAGUGCUGGGAUUACAGGCGUGAGCCACCGCGCACAGUCUAUAAUACUGAUUUUUAACCAAUUUAGGAGGGAAAUGUCAGAUAGGAGGCAUGGUACAAGGAUAUUUAUGGAAUUCAUUACCACUUCACUAAGAAAACAUGAUAUAAAUUGUCCUUUGAAAGCUACUUUGGUAUAAAAAAAUCUAAAGUGCCCAUAAGUAUGCAUUCAUUAUUAGACACAAAUUACAACCUUACAACCUACUAUGUUUAUUUCAUUAAAGUGUCUCUUUUAGGCCGGGUGUGGUGGCUCACGCCUGUAAUCCCAACACUUUGGGAGGCUGAGGCAGGUGAAUCAUGAGAUCAGGAGUUCGAGACCAGCCUGAACAACAUGAUGAAACCCGUCUCUACUAAAAAUACAAAAAAAUUUAGCGGGGUUUGGUGGCACACACCUGUAAUCCCAGCUAUUUGGGAGGCUGAGGCAGGAGAUCACUUGAACCCAGGAUGCGGAGGUUGCAGUGAGCUGAGAUCACGCCACUGCACCCCAGCCUAGGUGACAGAGCAAGACUGUCUCAAAAAUAAAUAAAUAAAUAAAUAAAUAAAUAAAAUAAAGUGUUUCUUUUAAACUGGUAUUGCCUAAGGUGUAUUCUUUAUAAAACUUAGAAUUGUUAAAUAUUUUAAGAUUCCUUUGAAAGUGUUUUUGCAUUGAUGGUUUAAAUCAGUGAUAUCAAACUUUCCUGAUCCUAUGUGCCCAGAAAAAUGGGCAGGGGAAAGGAGGCAGCAUGGAACCUCAUUUUUUUGUGUGUAUCUGUGUGUACACGUGAGUGCACAUGUGUAUAUGUGUGGGGCCACAUGUGUUUUGUAUACGGUAUAUGCAUGAAAAUGUACCUUUGUACCUUAUACACAAAAACAAAUUAAACAAUGGCAUAAGCAGCAAUAUAAAUAAAAAAUGCUAAUACUUUCCUGCCAUAUUCCAAAAUAAA